GCUGCUCUUGGAGAGGUCACUCCGGAGACGGCGUUGGUUUUGGGGUGUGGGGGGUUGGUGGCACUAUGUGGCGCGUCUGUGCGCGACGGGCUCAGAAUGUAGCCCCAUGGGCGGGACUCGAGGCUCGGUGGACGGCCUUGCAGGAGGUACCCGGAACUCCACGAGUGACCUCGCGAUCUGGCCCGGCUCCCGCUCGUCGCAACAGCGUGACUACAGGGUAUGGCGGGGUCCGGGCACUGUGCGGCUGGACCCCCAGUUCUGGGGCCACGCCGCGGAACCGCUUACUGCUGCAGCUUUUGGGGUCGCCCGGCCGCCGCUAUUACAGUCUUCCCCCGCAUCAGAAGGUUCCAUUGCCUUCUCUUUCCCCCACAAUGCAGGCAGGCACCAUAGCCCGUUGGGAAAAAAAAGAGGGGGACAAAAUCAAUGAAGGUGACCUAAUUGCAGAGGUUGAAACUGAUAAAGCCACUGUUGGAUUUGAGAGCCUGGAGGAGUGUUAUAUGGCAAAGAUACUUGUUGCUGAAGGUACCAGGGAUGUUCCCAUCGGAGCGAUCAUCUGUAUCACAGUUGGCAAGCCUGAGGAUAUUGAGGCCUUUAAAAAUUAUACACUGGAUUCCUCAGCAGCACCUACCCCACAAGCGGCCCCAGCACCAACCCCUGCUGCCACUGCUUCGCCACCUACACCUUCUGCUCAGGCUCCUGGUAGCUCAUAUCCCCCUCACAUGCAGGUACUUCUUCCUGCCCUCUCUCCCACCAUGACCAUGGGCACAGUUCAGAGAUGGGAAAAAAAAGUGGGUGAGAAGCUAAGUGAAGGAGACUUACUGGCAGAGAUAGAAACUGACAAAGCCACUAUAGGUUUUGAAGUACAGGAAGAAGGUUAUCUGGCAAAAAUCCUGGUCCCUGAAGGCACAAGAGAUGUCCCUCUAGGAACCCCACUCUGUAUCAUUGUAGAAAAAGAGGCAGAUAUAUCAGCAUUUGCUGACUAUAGGCCAACCGAAGUAACAGAUUUAAAACCACAAGUGCCACCACCUACCCCACCCCCGGUGGCCGCUGUUCCUCCAACUCCCCAGCCUUUAGCUCCUACACCUUCAGCACCCUGCCCAGCUACUCCUGCUGGACCAAAGGGAAGGGUGUUUGUUAGCCCUCUUGCAAAGAAGUUGGCAGUAGAGAAAGGGAUUGAUCUUACACAAGUAAAAGGGACAGGACCAGAUGGUAGAAUCACCAAGAAGGAUAUCGACUCUUUUGUGCCUAGUAAAGUUGCUCCUGCUCCGGCAGCUGUUGUGCCUCCCACAGGUCCUGGAAUGGCACCAGUUCCUACAGGUGUCUUCACAGAUAUCCCAAUCAGCAACAUUCGUCGGGUUAUUGCACAGCGAUUAAUGCAAUCAAAGCAAACCAUACCUCAUUAUUACCUUUCUAUCGAUGUAAAUAUGGGAGAAGUUUUGUUGGUACGGAAAGAACUUAAUAAGUUCUUCUUGUCUUUCCAGAUAUUAGAAGGGAGAAGCAAAAUUUCUGUCAAUGACUUCAUCAUAAAAGCUUCAGCUUUGGCAUGUUUAAAAGUUCCCGAAGCAAAUUCUUCUUGGAUGGACACAGUUAUAAGACAAAAUCAUGUUGUUGAUGUCAGUGUUGCGGUCAGUACUCCUGCAGGACUCAUCACACCUAUUGUGUUUAAUGCACAUAUAAAAGGAGUGGAAACCAUUGCUAAUGAUGUUGUUUCUUUAGCAACCAAAGCAAGAGAGGGUAAACUACAGCCACAUGAAUUCCAGGGUGGCACUUUUACGAUCUCCAAUUUAGGAAUGUUUGGAAUUAAGAAUUUCUCUGCUAUUAUUAACCCACCUCAAGCAUGUAUUUUGGCAAUUGGUGCUUCAGAGGAUAAACUGGUCCCUGCAGAUAAUGAAAAAGGGUUUGAUGUGGCUAGCAUGAUGUCUGUUACACUCAGUUGUGAUCACCGGGUGGUGGAUGGAGCAGUUGGAGCCCAGUGGCUUGCUGAGUUUAGAAAGUACCUUGAAAAACCUAUCACUAUGUUGUUGUAACUAACUCAAGAAUUUCUAAACUCUCCCAGGUCACACUGAUUCAUUCUUAACAAGAUAUUUAUAUGUUAUUAAACAGGUGGUUCUUUUUAUUUUAACCAGUUAUUUUUAUUAUUGAGUCUGUCCAGAUAAGUUAUUUAUAAUGGGCAUUACUGAAUUUUUAAAAUGCCGAUUACACCCAAAUAUUGUGCACAUUUAAUAAUCAGACACCAGAUUUUUAGCUCUGUACUCCUAAUUAAGGGACAUGUAUGUGGCCUUGCCUAGCCCUUUGGUGAUAAGUACUUCCUCUAGGAAAUGUACGAUAGGUAGAAUUGUGGUUCCCUAAAGACAAGUACAUAAAGGUGACCCUGAUGAAACCUUGAAGUUCUGAAAUUUAACUGCCUAAAAUGUUCUCCUUAGAUGUGAGAGAAAGAGAAAUCAGAAAAAUUAAUUCUCUUGGGGGAAGGGCUUGAAUUGAAGCUUUACUUUAGAAUUUAGCCCUGGUUUGAAAUUUUCCAUUACAUGAUCUUGGUUUAUCAUCGAUGGGAAGGGUAGAAAACUUCAAGGAAAAUAAGUGAAAUUUUAAAAGUCAGCAUUUUCUUAGACCUCUUCAGCUGAUUGUUUAUUUUUCUAUGAAUUCCUACACAUGGUUAUUCCCCCCUACUUGAGAUAAUCUAAAUAUAAACCAGCUACUUGAUGUAACUGAGAAUUUGUGUGGAUAUUUAUUUAAACAAAUGUGUAAUUUUGAGUACAGAAUUCAACAGUUACCUCCAAAAAAGAAACAUUGUUAAUAUAAUUUAACAGAAGUUGUGAAACUAAAAUUUUCUAAGAUUAACUGGUAGUUCAUUGUAAAUGAACAUAAUGAACAGAAUUUAUGACUCCACUGUGGAAAAUGCUAUCAAAUAACUAAGGAAUAUAUAUGGAAUAAGUGUACAUAUGUAAAAUAUUGUUACUAGAGUUAGAUAUGUGCCAAAGUCCAUUUAUCCCAAAUCCUGUCUGAAAAGGAGGGGUACAUUGGUAAACAUUUUGGAGUGCUUAAAAAUGCCAAAAACAAAAUGGUAAUUUCUACUUUGAUAAAGUAAAAAAGUUAAAUGUGUGUAAAAAAGUGUUCUGUGUCCUUCUACUCCAGCAUCGUCUCAUGUAAAAUAAGAAAGCCCUAAAAUACUAUUGGAGAGAAAAAAUUAACUAGGUUGCUACUUUAUUUGCCUAAAUACUUUUUUCUAUUUUGUUAGAUUUUGCCUUUCUUUUGGAAGGAAGGAGGCGAUAUUCUGGAUUAUAAAAAUGAAUUGGGAACAUUAUCACAAUUCCAGACUUUCUAUUAAUAUUUAUGUGUUUUAAUAAACGUUUGAAAUUAUUUAUGACUACUUAAAAUGAAUCUGACCAGUGCUUCCUGGUAUAUGUAAUAUGUGGAGUUAGCCCCUGAAAUUUGCUUUAAGUGUUUCAGUGUUGAAUCUGUUUCUAAAUAUUCAUUAUUACAUGGUACACAAGUGACACUCCAUAUAUUCCACACAGACUUUUACCUUGCUGUAUUAUUAUGAAAACAAUACAUUAAUUUGAUUUUUCAGUAAUUAGUAAUUUUAGGUUGAAGAUUAUCCAAAAGAAACAAGCUUAUCACAAGGGACCAUCAUCAAUAUGAUCCAAAUCUGGUUCAAACAUUCAAAACUUCAAAGAUAAUUCAUCUUUCGCUAAUGCUUGUGGUUCUGUUGUUCCCUUGAAAAAAAAUAAAAACAGUUGCCUUCUAAUAAACAUUGUUGAGUUAAAAAUUAAUCUGAGCUAUAAUCUAAAUCGAUUCAGUCUCUUACCAGAACUGAAAGAAAAAAGUUAGAAAUAGUGUUUUUGGUUCAUAUGAUUAUUUAAAAAUUAAAGUAUAAAUCUUCAAUAUGUCUGGUUUAA